CGGCGUUCAAGAUGUCGAAGCGAGGACGUGGUGGGUCCUCUGGUGCGAAAUUCCGGAUUUCCUUGGGUCUUCCGGUAGGAGCUGUAAUCAAUUGUGCUGACAACACAGGAGCCAAAAACCUGUAUAUCAUCUCCGUGAAGGGGAUCAAGGGACGGCUGAACAGACUUCCCGCUGCUGGUGUGGGUGACAUGGUGAUGGCCACAGUCAAGAAAGGCAAACCAGAGCUCAGAAAAAAGGUACAUCCAGCAGUGGUCAUUCGACAACGAAAGUCAUACCGUAGAAAAGAUGGCGUGUUUCUUUAUUUUGAAGAUAAUGCAGGAGUCAUAGUGAACAAUAAAGGCGAGAUGAAAGGUUCUGCCAUUACAGGACCAGUAGCAAAGGAGUGUGCAGACUUGUGGCCCCGGAUUGCAUCCAAUGCUGGCAGCAUUGCAUGAUUCUCCAGUAUAUUUGUAAAAAAUAAAAAAAAAAACUAAACCCAUUAAAAAGUAUUUGUUUGCAGUGCUUGUCUCCCUGUUCACUUCCAGGGUUCAAGCGAUUCUCCUGCCUCAGCCUCCUAAGUAGCUGGGAUUACAGGCACCUGCCGUCAUGCCUGGCUAGUUUUUGUAUUUUUGGUGGAGACAGGGUUUCACCAUGUUUGCCAAACGACUCAAACUCCUGAUCUCAAGUGAUCUGCCCACCCAGGCCUCUACAGUGUUUUUGACAUACCCUGACCAUCACUUUUCUGAAAUGGAAACUCUGGGCAUUUUUUUUUUAAAGCAAUCCUUGCUUUUUUGUGAGUUUGCAGACUUUCAGCAUCUUCCAAUUGCUGUAUUUACAAUUUUGGCCUCAAAAAGUAUUAUUUGGGUUUUGAGUCCCAAAAAUAAUAGUAGAUACUGCUCAAUGACUGGCUAUACAUGGUAGCUUCUCCUGGAGUGAGGAAGGCAUUCAAAUGGCUGGGCGCGGUAGCUGGCACCUGUAAUCCCAACACUUUCGGAGGCCAAGGCAGGCAGAUCAUGAGGUCAGGAGUUCAAGACCAGGCUGACCAACGUGGUGAAACCUCCUCUUUUCUAAAAAUACAAAAAUUAGCUGGGCGUGGUGGCGCACCGCCUGUAAUCUCAGCUACUGAGAGAAUCGCUUGAACCUGGGAGGUGGAGUUUGCAGCGAGUCGAGAUUGCACCAUUGUACUCCAUCCAGCCUGGGCAACGGAGCAAGAUUCCGUUCCCGCCCCCGCCCCAAAAAAAGGCAUUGAAGUUAAGAUAGACUAUAUAGUUAGAUCCUGGACACACACAUGGAUUUUGAGGAAUGAUGUGAGUUUGUUUAUGUAUGUACAUUUUAGCAGUUAACAGAUUUGGAGUAAAUUGAAUAUUUAUAAAACAACAGUAAUUGCCAUGUAGGUUUACUGUCAUAGUGGAAGAUGAUUAAGUUGAUGGUACCUACAGGUAUUUUGCUAUGAAAAUGUUUUGACAAACAGGAUGAUCGUGUAAUUUAUGUUCCAAGCUCUAGUUUGAGAAUGGAAGAAUGUGGUAAAUUUUUGCCAACUGAACAGGCAUAAAGCGCUGAUAAUAAGGGACUUGGCCUUAAGGUAGGAGGUUGUUAGCAUUUCUUUCUAAACGUGUAAGAGUUUAUUUAGGUGACACCCAGCGUUUUGGAAAAAUGGGUGUUUGUUUAGAACAAUAAUUUGGAGGGAAGUGGACUAAACAGGGUUUUUAGAUUAAGGUUUGUGUUUAUGUAUCUGUAUCUGCAAAUACUCAGCCAUAAAUGUUUCUACCUGUAAGUUGGGUAUAAUACAAGCUCCACUUGGUAUCAAAAAGGACUACCCUUAGUGUCUUCCAUGACUAGUUAUGGAAUGUACCAGACCUAGAGAGGAGUUGUUCUAACCUGGAGCUUUUGAAAAUGUUUCCGGUCCAUACCCUAGACCAAUUAAGUCAGACUGCAGAAUAGGACUCAGACAUCAGAAUUGUGAAGCUCCCAGGAGAUGUCAAGGUAUACCCAAGACUGAGAACCAGUACCCUGUCUAGACUGAACCAGGCUUGGUUUUAGAAGUAUUAAAUCUCGCCUGGGUACGGUGGCUCACACCUAUAAUCCCAGCACUUUGGGAGGCUGAGGUGGGUGGAUCAUCUGAGGUCAGGAGAGUGAGACCAGCCUGUCCAACAUGUUGAAACCCCAUCUCUACUAUACAAAAUUAGCCAGGCAUGGUGGUGCAUGCUGUAAUCCCAGCUACUUGGGAGGCUGAGGCAGGAGAAUUGCUUGAACCCCGGAGAUGGAGGUUGCAGUGAGCUGAGGUCGCACGAUUGUGCUCCAGCCUGGGCAACCAGUGAAACUCUGGGGGGAAAGAAAAAAAAUGUAUUAAAUCUCUAGUUUUAGAGAGUUACACCAUAACAUCCCUGAGUAUGGUCAAUUUCAAGUCAGCUUUAGUGUGACAAGCCCCUAGGCCCACCAUUUAUGUCUUUAUAUAUUAUGGCAAUAUAUGAUCCUUAUAUAUUAACCACUAAUCGCUGCUGUUUUUGAAUGUUAUCUUUUCUGAGGCAGUCUUGCUCUGUCACACAGGCUGGAGUGCAGUAACACCACUGAAGCUCACUGUAACUUUGAACUGCUGGACUUGGAAUCCUCCUGCUGUGGCCUUCAAAGGGCUGCAAUUACAAGUGUGAGCCACUGCAUCCCACCUCACAUUUUAUUCUUUGGAGAUUUUUUUUGACUUGGAUUAAAAAACUUUAUAUUUACACUUCA